GAGCGGCAGGUGGGGCCGGCAGAUCUUCUUUGCGCAUGCGGAAACCGCUGCCCGCUUCCACCUCUAACCCAGGCUCAGAGUAGCUGCUGUUUCUGAGAGAACGAUUCGUAGGACAGCCCCUGACGCCAUUCCCUUUUGCCCUUCUUUCUGCGGGCCUUUCCGGUACUUGAGCGGUGUCCAGAGCGUGGCCAGUUCUCGUCUAUCUGGCUGCCUUUAGGGAGCGGUGCCUAGCGUUGGCCAAUAGUUGGCUGUCGAAAGUGCCGGCCCCCGCGCCGGCGCCUGCAGCAGCCGGGUGGGAAGGCUCAAGAUGGCGUGCUUGUUGGAGACCCCAAUCCGCAUGAGCGUCCUUUCGUUUUUUUAAAGAAAAAGACGACUUUCACCUUUCACUAUGUUGCUCUUGAACCAGGACCAGGAAUGAAAGUUACUGGGAGAUAACUUCGAAGGAUUUUGCAACAAAUUCGAGCUGUCCGACUCUGAGAAUGGAAGUAACAGCUAGCAGUCGCCACUAUGUUGACAGGCUAUUUGACCCUGAUCCCCAGAAAGUUCUACAAGGUGUCAUAGACAUGAAAAAUGCUGUAAUUGGAAACAACAAGCAGAAAGCCAAUCUCAUUGUUUUAGGAGCUGUUCCAAGAUUGUUGUACUUGCUUCAGCAAGAAACCUCAAGCACAGAGCUGAAAACUGAAUGUGCAGUGGUGUUGGGAAGUCUUGCUAUGGGUACUGAAAACAAUGUCAAGUCUCUACUGGACUGCCAUAUUAUCCCUGCCUUAUUGCAAGGACUACUGUCCCCAGACCUGAAGUUUAUUGAAGCUUGCCUCCGAUGCCUGCGUACCAUCUUCACCAGUCCUGUCACUCCAGAGGAGCUACUGUAUACAGAUGCCACAGUGAUACCACACCUCAUGGCACUGCUUAGCAGGUCCCGCUAUACCCAGGAGUACAUCUGUCAGAUCUUCUCACACUGCUGUAAAGGGCCAGAUCAUCAAACAAUUUUAUUUAACCACGGUGCAGUUCAGAAUAUUGCUCACCUACUAACCUCACUGUCCUACAAAGUUCGAAUGCAAGCACUGAAAUGUUUCUCAGUUUUAGCUUUUGAAAACCCCCAGGUAUCGAUGACCCUGGUAAAUGUUUUGGUUGAUGGAGAAUUGUUACCACAGAUUUUUGUGAAGAUGUUACAGAGGGAUAAGCCUAUUGAGAUGCAGCUCACAUCAGCAAAAUGUUUAACUUACAUGUGUAGAGCUGGAGCAAUUCGGACAGAUGAUAACUGUAUUGUAUUAAAGACAUUACCUUGUUUGGUUCGAAUGUGCAGUAAGGAGAGAUUACUAGAGGAGAGAGUUGAAGGAGCUGAGACACUUGCCUAUCUGAUUGAACCAGAUGUUGAGCUACAGAGAAUCGCUAGCAUAACUGAUCACCUCAUUGCCAUGCUUGCUGAUUAUUUCAAGUAUCCCAGCUCAGUGAGUGCCAUCACUGAUAUUAAAAGGCUUGAUCAUGAUUUAAAACAUGCUCACGAACUCCGCCAGGCUGCAUUCAAGCUCUAUGCCUCUCUUGGAGCAAAUGAUGAAGACAUCCGGAAGAAGAUCAUUGAGACUGAAAAUAUGAUGGACCGAAUUGUGACUGGCUUGUCUGAGUCUAGUGUCAAGGUGCGGUUAGCUGCCGUCAGAUGUUUGCACAGUUUAUCCAGAUCUGUGCAGCAGCUUCGAACCAGUUUCCAGGAUCAUGCUGUUUGGAAACCUUUAAUGAAGGUUUUACAAAAUGCACCAGAUGAAAUCCUAGUGGUAGCAUCUUCCAUGCUGUGUAAUCUUCUUCUUGAAUUUUCUCCAAGCAAAGAGCCAAUUUUGGAAUCAGGAGCCGUAGAGCUACUUUGUGGAUUAACUCAGAGUGAAAAUCCUGCUUUACGAGUGAAUGGAAUUUGGGCUUUAAUGAAUAUGGCAUUUCAGGCUGAACAAAAAAUAAAAGCAGAUAUUUUACGAAGCUUGAGUACUGAACAGCUAUUCCGGUUAUUAUCAGAUUCAGAUUUGAAUGUGCUGAUGAAGACAUUGGGACUUCUUAGAAAUCUCCUCUCCACUCGUCCUCAUAUAGAUAAAAUAAUGAGUACUCAUGGAAAGCAAAUUAUGCAAGCCGUCACUCUUAUUCUAGAAGGGGAACAUAACAUUGAGGUCAAAGAGCAGACACUGUGCAUCUUAGCCAACAUAGCGGAUGGGACAACAGCAAAAGAUCUUAUUAUGACCAAUGAUGAUAUCCUACAGAAAAUCAAGUAUUACAUGGGCCAUUCACAUGUUAAACUGCAGCUUGCAGCCAUGUUUUGUAUAUCAAACCUCAUAUGGAAUGAAGAGGAAGGUUCACAAGAACGCCAGGAUAAAUUACGAGACAUGGGCAUCGUAGAUAUUCUACACAAACUGAGUCAGUCACCAGAUUCAAACCUUUGUGACAAGGCAAAGAUGGCACUGCAGCAGUACCUGGCAUGAUGGGAGUGCCCCUGGGCACCUGCGAGCAUCCCACCUCCUUGUUUAAGGAAGUACAGGAACCAGCCUCAUUUGAUUCCUUCUAUUUGCACAAGUCACCUUGGACUGCAGGGAGCUGUUUUGCAAAAGCAGUUUAGUAGGCUUAGAUCUCAAAUUCAUCUUGAGAACAUUUUUUUGAGGUAGUAAUUUCCUCAGAAGACUCUUGUGUUUUGUUUUGGUUUUUUUUUCUGAGCUACUCGGACUCUUUAUUAGAACAAUCAAUCAUUUUCCUUUGGACCUACAAUUUUUGCCUAUGCUGCAGCCACUUUGUGAGUGAGAAUGAAUAUGUCUGUGUGAACACACAGGCAUGCGUGUGUAUGUGCACGUACAUGGGCCAGAAUGAAUGGAUGUGUGUGUGUGAGGGAUACCUCAGAUUUUUCUUUUCUUAUUUUGUGUGAAAAUCUCUUUUCUACAGAUUUUCCAGGGUUUAAGCAUUGCUUGCUGUAUAAAAAACUUUACUGAAUUAUAUACAGUUUGAAUGAAAUGUUAUUUUAAAAACAAAACAAUUGUUAAGUGUUCCAUAAAGGUUAUGUUGAAUUUUGGUCAGAUGAAUAUUUGUAAGUAAAAAAUAUAUGCAUUUCUGAACCUCAACUUACAUAGAUUUUCUUUAUAUAAAAAAAAAGAAAAAAAAAGAAAAAGUUGGCUAUAGUUGGCCUGAUUAACAGGCACUAUACAUGGUGCUGUGCAAAAUAGUAAGCUAGCAUCUUACUGCCGUCAAUAUUAGCAGGUACAGAGCCUUUUUUCAUCCUAAUUCAGUAAGUUCUCAGGCUUCCAAGUCAAAUGGAGAAGUAAAGUGAGGCAACAGAUUCACCAUAGGCUUUUUGAAGCAUCAAAGGGAAAUAUAACUACUGAUAGUGAAAGCCCAGCCAUGACCCAGAUGGGCUUACCCUUGACAGGAACUGGGGACCAAGAGCCUCCCAAUUGCCCUAACUCCUGUCAUUGGUAUUAGCAAUAUCUGGCCAGAUUUAGAACCAGUCAUGGAAACUUGUGCUCAAACUAAAAGUAGGUCAUCACUUCCCAGAAACAGAAUACCUUGUGCUUCCUGAAACAGCAUAUAUCACUGUGAAACUAAAGAAUAUUCUACAGACACCCCUGUAGAAAGAAACAAAGAACAGGAUAGUUUAGAAAGCUUUCUGUUAGCUGUAUUCAGCAAAUUUCAUACUAGUUGCUCAGGACUGCUAGUUGGUAUGCUUUUGUAAAACGAGAUUGAAAUUUAAUAAAAGAUGCAACUAAAAUCUUUCCUGCAUGAAGCUAAAAGCACUCAAGUUGAGAGAGGGGCAAGGGAAUCUCCCCAGGAUGACUGAAGAUGACUUCUUUUUACAGCAAGUACUGUUAGCCUUUCUGCACCCCUUAGCUUGGCCCCUGCUCCAACUUCUGGGUCAGCAGCAAGGUGAACUCAACAGAAGUUGCUCUUGACUGUUUGAAGGUAGAAGCAGCCUACCUUUUCUCUUUGCUAAAAGAAGGUCAAAGGCUUCGCAACCAGGAUGCAAGGUCUGCGGUCCAGAAGCUUGCGGUGAGUGUGUGCCACUGAUGGAGCUCCAAGCCCACCCACCAGCCACUCCUGAUGGGGUUGCUCACACUGCAGCUGCCCUAUCACCACCCUGCACGUUCCUUGGAAGAUUUAAAUGUUUGGUUGCAAAUGAAUGUUUUAAAAAUGUAUUUAAUGCAAUUUUUCCUGCUCUCAACAUGACCACCCAAGAUUCAAACACAGAGACUUCCAAGUUACUAUUUUUUCAGAACAUCACCGAUUUUAAAAUCUGUCACAACAGGACUUGGUUUUGUGCAGAUAUCAGAGUGCUAAUGUGAGAAACCCAGUUAAAAGAAAACUUAGUUUAUUGGGAAGAAAGCCUCAGGCCCACUCGUUUCUAGAACUGUGAAAAUAUCCUUGGUUGGCAUUUUUAACACAAAACACUAUAGUGUUGGUAUUAAAUAGUACUAGGUAAAUAUAAAGAAACCAAUAAUGAAUUGCUGAGACAAUCUUGAACCCAAAUAGCAUUAGAAAGCUGAAGGCCCAAUGAAAUAACACUUUCACACUUAAACUCUGUGGAUAAAUUUUGCCUGUGGGUAUAAACAGAUGGUCAAAUUAAAAAUGCUUUACUAUAAUUAACUUUUCUGAUUUGAAUGAAGGGAAAUGUAUUUAUUGAAACAAAGCUGUUUGCUGCUUUAUGCAGGUGCAGUGUUCAGUCAGCAAGGAAGUGGGAAGAGUGGACAUGGUAUUGUGUCUACACCCAAGUUCUUAACUAAGCUUCUCGCUCUAAUACUGCAUUCUGUUUCUCCUUUUGUGCCCUGAUUGUAAUCCAAAAUUUAUGAACUAGAAAAGAAUGUCCAAUUUAAUAAGUUGCAUUUUUUUUUCUUUAAGCACUUUAUUCAGAACAAUACAUGUUCUUCUGGUAGUGUUUGGAUAAUAUGAUUUUAACACAUGCUAAUAAAAGCCAAGAAAAAUCAUGGCAACUUCUAAAAA